GAGACCCGGUCCCCGUCCCUGGGGCCUGGCCAGAGUCGCUCGCACCCCUUCUGCCCCGCGAGCUGGCGGCGGAAGCUGGGGGCGUCUCCACCGCCUUAGGGGGUAGACGCGCGCUCCGUGUGGGGUACGGUUCACGAUCAUUUUCACGACUUUUUAAAGGCAGUAAUCGUUCUGGUCACUGGGACACAGCUGCACUCGCCCAUUCUAAAAAGUCAGCGCCCUCAGGCCCGCGGGUAACCACCUCCUCCUGAGCGCGGUGACCAGGUCACAGGCUGUCCCUCGUGCCUCAGUGUUCUCAUCUGUAUGUCGAGCACUGCACAGAAUCGGCUCAUGCGCUGAGGCUUUCACGCCUGUGAUGGAAGAGACAGAGAAGGGGGUGGCCUCUCCUCUCCCUGGGGACCUGCCAUUCUCAGCACAGGCACAUGGCAGGCAGCAGCCUCCCUUCUGCCAGCAGAGGGGCUUAAUGCACCCCGUUCCAUUUGUAAUUCAUGUGCAUUGAGCUCACUGGAUGAGUCAGUUGGGAUAUAUAUUCCUCCCUGGGUCUGCCCCAUUUUAUGGGGUGUUGCUUAAUCAUUUGUGUUAUUCCAUUGACAUAAAAUAUUUAGCACUCAGAGAUCAUUUCUGGUCAGGAGAAAUGUGUGCAUUUUUAACCCAAAAUAGAAACCUUCAUAAAAGCAUCAUAGGUCUCCAUUCAAUAUUGACUAUAAUUGUUCACAUGCCCACACUGAAUGCUAACUUGGGCUCACCCUCAACACCCACCAGGUGGGUACUAUUAUUAUCACUCACAUUUGACCAGAGGGAUUGUUUGAUUAGGGUGAAGUAGUUGAGAGUUCAGACCCAGGAGACAGCCUGCCUGCUUCGAAUCCUGGCCCAACCCCUGGCCCUGUGUGACCUUGGGCAAGUGACUGUAUCUCUCUGUGCUAUUGUUUUCUUAUUAAUAAAAUGGGGGAUAUAAUGAUACCUACCUCUUAGGGUUGUUCUCAGCGUUGAGUACAAAUGCCUGCGGAUCAGUGCCUGGCUCAUGGUAAAUGCAUGUCGGUGUUAGCUAGUGUUUUCUUCAGUCUCAAAAUGUUUAAUAAAUGCCUUCCGUGAGCCAGGCACCAUGGAUCGGCAGUACCCAUGAUAGAUGAGGCUCUGCUUGCAUGGGAGAGACAGAGAAUAAAUGAAUAAACAAGAAAAGACCAGAUGAGAGUGGCUUUAAAGCCAAUAAAACAGGGAAAUGGUGAAUGGAGCAACUGGGGAGAACUGUCACCAAAGUCAGGGAAUCAGGGAAGCCUUCCCCAAAGAGGUGGCAUUUGAACUGGGACCUGAGUGGUGAAGCAGCCAGCCAUGGGAAGGGUUUGGGGAACAAGAUAUGCAAAGGCCCUGUUGUGGAAAUAAGCCAGCUGUGGUUGAGGAACAACAGCAAGGCAGCCAGUGUGGCUGGAGUGGAGUGAGCAGGGUGGGCCAGUGGUGAGGGAGAACAGGCCAGAGAGGGGGAUUAGCAGCAGGCCUUGUAGGGCCUUUUAUGGCAUAGAAGGAGCUCUGAAGCAAUGAAGUGCCUUGCCAUGUGUCACAUACCAGCCGAGACAGUCUGCCUAACUCGGGAGCCAAAGCUCACUGCUGGGCUUGAGGCCCCUGUAAGAGGACAAUGUAACCCAGGCUGGUAUGGGCACAUUCUGCAUUUCCACUUAAACUCAGAUGGCAAGCCCAUCAAACCUUGGUGCCAUGGCUGCCCUGGUAAUUCCUGGCUGACCAGUGUAACCAGGGAGCUGGCCCAUGACCUGGGUGGCAGCUGAGUAGCCAGGACUAAUGCGACCAAGAGUCAGCCUUCUUCCUGUGACUCAUCCAGGUGCACCCUGCGACAUCUGAAGGUCAGGCUUUCAGCCGCUGUGGCUUCCACUUCCAACUGGCUCCACGUCCCCAGGGAGGGAUCACAUAGAGCUUUGCCAACACAUUCUAUUGCGUGUUUAAUGUUCCUGUGAAUGGGCCCUUGAGAUUUCUCUCUCUCCCAUCCACACAGAGCUUAGAGGCAAAGUUAAGAGACUCAUCAGAUUCUGAGCUGCUGCGGGAUAUUUUGCAGAAGACUGUGAGGCAUCCUGUGUGUGUGAAGCACCCGCCGUCAGUCAAGUAUGCCUGGUGCUUUCUCUCAGAACUCAUCAAAAAGAGACAAGAUCUCUGUUGCCCAGGCUGUCCUCGAACUCCUGGGCUCAAGCAGUCCUCCCACGUCAGCCUUUAGAGUAGCUGGAACUAUUCGACACACACCACCACGCCCAACGAAGUGAGUAUUUUAUAUACCAGCUGGCCGGUAUUACACCAUUCCAUCCCAAAUCUCCCCUCCAAACUUGGUGAAAAUCAUCUGGCCAUUUUUACAGAUUAGAACGAAAGCAAACAAGCUCUCACUCUGUCUGCCCCCAGCACGAGGCUGUCCACACGGAGCCUUUGGACAAACUGUACGAGGUGCUCACGGAGACUCUGAUGGCCAAGGAGUCCACCCAGGGCCACCGGAGCUAUUUGCUGGUAUGAGAAAGGCACCCUCCUCCCCCUCACAGCCCAGAUACCCUUCCUGCACAGACAAAGUGAAAACGUGGGUGUGGGUUCAAAUCCUGACUCACCCAUUCUGCAGUCUUAGACAUGAGGUCCAUUAACCUUCUUUAGCCUCAGUUUCCCUGUCUGUAAAUCAAGCACUUCAACAACAACAGCAUGUCUCGUGGGGUUGUUGGGCAUUUGUCCAAUAGGUGACACACACUACCUGCUUCACAAGGACCUGGUGCCCAGUCCUCAAAGAAUACUUGACAGGGCUGGACAUGGUCUCUCAUGCCUGUAAUCCCAGCACUUUGGGAGGCCAAGGCGGGUGGAUCUGAGGUCAGGAGUUCGAGACCAGCCUGGCCAAUAUGGUGAAACCCUGUCUCUACUAAAAAUACAAAAAUUAGGCCAGGCGUGGUGGCUCAUGUCUGUAAUCCCAGCACAUUGGGAGGCUGAGGCAAGGGGAUCACCUGAGGUCAGGAGUUUGAGACCAGCUUGGCCAACAUGGUGAAAAUCCAUCUUUACUAAAAAUACAAAAAUUAACGGGGUGUGGUAGUGGGCGCCUGUAAUCCCAGUUACUCGGGAGGCUGAGGCAGGAGAAUCUCUUGAACCCGGGAGGUGGAGGUUGUAGUGAGCCGAGAUCGUGCUAUUGCACUCCGGCCUCGGCAACGAGAGUGAAUCUGUGUCUCAAAAAAAAGUACAAAAAUUAGCUAGACAUGGUGGCACACGCCUGUAGUCACAGCUACCUGGGCAGGUGAGGCAGGAGAAUUGCUUGAACCCAGGAGGCAGAUGUUGCAGUAAGCCAAGAUCGUGCCACUGACUCCAGCCUGGGUGACAGAGCUCAAAAAAAAAAAAAAAAUGAGAUAAAACAUAGAUACAGAAAACCACAAAGGAAAAACAUAGCAUAUUGAAUCAUCACAAGGCAGCCACCUCUUCAUAGCCACACCUGGCCCCUGGCCACCACUGACCUGUGCUCCAUCGCCAGAAUUCCGUUGUCUCAGGAAUGUUCAAUAGAUGGAAUCCUGUGUGGCCUGAGAUGAGUGUCUUUCAUGCCGCGUGACACCCUUGAGGCCCGUGCAACUGUUGGUAUGUCAACAGUUAGCUGCUUCUCAUUGCUGAGUGGCGAUUGGUCCUGUCAUGGUUUAUUCAGCCAUGUGGUGGAUGGCUACUUGUCUUCUAAGCCACUUGCCUUCUGAUCGCUGGACUGACUCUCUCGCCCUCUCUUGGUGCAGUCCUCAGGAGGCUCAGUCACACUCUCCAAGAGCACAGCCAUCAUCUCCCACGGUACCACAGGCCUGGUCACAUGGGAUGCCGCCCUCUACCUUGCAGAAUGGGCCAUCGAGAACCCGGCAGCCUUCAUUAACAGGUGACCUUGGGGCACAGGGCAGGGCACCGAGGCAGGCUUACCCUGGUGCAGUCGAAAACACGGUCCCCUUUCCUCCCGCCAGGACUGUCCUAGAGCUUGGCAGUGGUGCCGGCCUCACAGGCCUUGCCAUCUGCAAGAUGUGCCGCCCCCGGGCAUACAUCUUCAGCGACCCUCACAGCCGGGUCCUCGAGCAGCUCCGAGGGAAUGUCCUUCUCAAUGGCCUCUCAUUAGAGGCAGACAUCACUGGCAACUUAGACAGCCCCAGGGUGACAGUGGCCCAGCUGGACUGGGACGUAGCAAUGGUCCAUCAGCUCUCUGCCUUCCAGCCAGAUGUUGUCAUUGCAGCAGACGUGCUGUAUUGCCCAGAAGCCAUCGUGUCGCUGGUCGGGGUCCUGCAGAGGCUGGCUGCCUGCCGGGAGCACAAGCGGGCUCCUGAGGUCUACGUGGCCUUUACCGUCCGCAACCCAGAGACGUGCCAGCUGUUCACCACCGAGCUAGGUGAACCCCCACGCCCACCCGGGCCUACAUGGUGCCCGAGCUGUCCCUGCAGGACUCCAGUGGAAGUGAAAGAACUGGGCGCUGGGGAAAAGCUAGGAUGCUCCACACUCCCACACUAUGCGGGGAACUCGGGCAGAGGCCGGCCGGGAUGGGAUCAGAUGGGAAGCGGAAGCUCAUCAUGACCAGAAACUGUUUCCCUAUGGAGAGCACUUGGAGAUGGCAAUGCUGAACCUCACACUGUAGGACUCACACAUGACUCCAAAGGGAUUGUGAGAAUCAAGUCACUCUCGUGGGAAGAAUUUUUAUAUGGGAAAGUGGAUAAAACUUUCAUUGGACUGGAAUGUUUGGAGAUUAUUAAACUCCAAAUCAGGAAUCAAAACUGCCCUCUAAUAAGACAUUAGCUGUCUAGGCGUGUGGGUGCCCCCUUUCUGCCAGCAGUUCUGGUUCUCAAGAAAAUCAUCAUAAAUCAGACAUGAAAAUUCUAGCUCCAAAAAUAGCAUUUUCUUUCUGCAAAUAAAAACGUGUGUAUCAAGGAUGACGUUCCCCCAACGUGGACACACUCGGUUCCUCAGAAAGCCAAGCCCGCUGCAGCUGCCACAUCCCUGGACACACUCGGUUCCUCACAAAGCCAAGCCCGCUGCAGCUGCCACAUCCCUGGACACACUCGGUUCCUCACAAAGCCAAGCCCGCUGCAGCUGCCACAUCCCUGGACACACUCGGUUCCUCACAAAGCCAAGCCCGCUGCAGCUGCCACAUCCCAGGGCUUAUGGUGCAGCAGGCGCUUUUUUCAAGACAGGAAUGAAAGUGUUAGGAACACGGCAGAAAGGUGACACCUGGAGACCAAAUGCAGGAUGAGGAGUACUGCAGAGGUCACAGGGAAGUCACAGAACAGUAAUACGCUAGCAGGGGCAUGGGGCAUGAAGAACAGAAGACAGGAAGCAUUUCAGAGACUCCAAAGAAGAAAUCAGGGCCAACCACAGCUUCCCGGGUCAUUCACCAGGUGACACCACUGCCGUCAUUUCAGCUUCUGGCCACUGGGAGGCGCUGCUCGAAAGGCUUUGCCCUGAGACUCCAAGAAGCUGCGGGAAGGACAGCAGGGGCCCUGGGGUUUUAGCCUCUGGCCCAGGAGUUAUGUGUCCAUAACCAAAGGGAGCACAGUCUGCACCCAGCUCUCAUCCCAUCAGAGCUGCUGAGACUCUUGCAGGUUCUUCCAGAACUGGCUUAGCUUGCCUGCAGGAUCAGAAAAGUUUGAGAAAAGCAUCUGCAAAAUGCUAAAGAGCAGAGCUUAACUCAUUGCCUGUCCCCACCCCAUCCCAGGUCACCACUUGGAUGACCCCAGGUCCCCGACCCAACAACAACCCCUCCCAAGUCCCUAACUCCCUCACUUGGACUUGAGACCCUUCACAACCCCCCUCACUUGGACUUGAGACCCUUCACAACCCAGCAGCGCUCCACUUCCAACUUGACAUCAUGCUUUCUGGAAACUUCCCCGUAUGUCCCACUUUCCCACACUUGGUGCCCUGGAGCACCUUCCGGCCUCUACAUGCUGUACGUUCCCCUGUGAGCACCCUCCUCUCGGCCUCUGGCCAACACAGUCCCACCCAUCUGUGGGUAACAAGGGGGUGUGGGUGUUCUUUUCAGCCUUGCUAAACUGUCUGAAUCAAGGAUCACAAACUACAGCCUGCAGGCCAAAUCCAGCCCACAGCCUGUGUUUGUAAAUAAAGCUUUGUUGGAACAAAGCCA